GUGGUUGGCCAUGGAUGGCAUGCUAAAAAAUCUGUUGCUCCGUAAGUACUGCGAACUGAUGGAGCUUUAAGUGAAGAGAAUGAUCAGCGUCCAAACUUGUCUCCUGAACAAAAGCAAGCCUGGGCCCUGGGCCUGGGUUGGAGCUCUGGAGUUUGGAUUUGUGAGAUGGGGCUGAGGGUGAUAUGACAGACAGUGUCUAGGGACAGGGCUAAAUGAAAAGCUGGGCAGACAGUCCCACUGUGGUGUUCAUCCAGUGGGAUGUGGGGAGAUGGGCAGAGUUCAAGUGUGAGACAGAGAACCCUGAGCCCAGGAGGACAGGGCUUGGCAGAGAAAGGAGGCAGUCUGCCAUAAUCUCCUGAGCCGCAAAGGUGUAGCUGCAGAUGCUUUUUAUAUGGUGCUUCCAGCCUUGACUGUGAGUGGGGAGGUGCCUGUUAAUGGGCCCAGGCUGUCUUGGACAAGCAGAUCUUUGUGUUUGGAAGUAGUGUCUGACGGCAGAGUAAAGGAUGGGUGUGAUGAGCCUGGAGAGACUGACACGGAGGUAAUUUUGGAGGAUGAUGAGUUAUUCAAUCAACAGAUACAAUGGAUUUAAGUCAUGCUAUAGAGGAAAUGGAAAGCAAGGAACAAAUGCAGGGUGGUUACUUAGGUAGCUGGAACAUAUAAGAGGAUUGAGAGAGAUGGAGAAAGGGAGGACGAAUUUAAGGACUCAAGCUUGGGUAUUUGAGAGAAUAAUGCCAUUAACUAAGAGAGGUAACAGAAAAGGAGAAUGUAGGAGAGACUAUAACCUUGAACUCUUGGGCUCAAGUUAUCCUCCUGCCUCAGUCUCUCAAGCGACUGAUGGAUCCAGUCCAUCAAAAUCCAUUGUUGCCUUCUUUCCCAGUAGCAGAAUUAUAACUGAGCAUACAACUGCCCAGCAACAUGAAAUUCCCCUGUCUCCUUUGCAAUUAGGUGUGGCUUUAUGAUGAAGUAUUUUCCAAUAGAAUGUAAGCAAAGGUGGUAUGUGUCUUCCAGGCCUAGUGCAUAGAACCUGUCAUGUGACCCCCUCAGAAUCCGCCACUCUCUUUCCCCUUUCUCAUGGGCUGGAAAGGUGAAUACUAGAGCAACCUUGGAAGCCACAUGUUGAAGAUGACAGAGCCACCUUCAACUUGGGUCCCUGACCUGAUUUGGGAGAAGAAAUAAGUUUUCAUUUUGGGGUCUUUUUUUUUUUUUUUUUUGAUGGAGUCUCAUUCUGUCGCCAGGCUGGAGUGCAAUGGCGUGAUCUCAGCUCACUGCAACCUCCACCUCCCAGGUUCAAGUAAUUCUCCUGCCUCAGCCUCCCGAGUAGCUGGGAUUGCAGGCACGUGCCACCACACCCAGCUAAUGUUUGUAUUUUCAGUAGAGACGAGGUUUCACCAUGUUGGCCAGGAUGGUCUCAAUAUCCUGAUCUGCCUGCCUCAGCCUCCCAAAGUGCUGGGAUUACAGGCAUGAGCUACCACACCGGCCCACUUUUUAUAGCAUUUUACAGUCACUCCUAACUAAUGCAUAUGGAACAGUUUGGGAGAUAGGGAAUAGGGAAGGUGAAGAAUUUGGUUUAUCACUCAAUGGUCAGUAUGAGCAUUGAAAUUAACUUAAUCCCCAGGGAAAAGAAAGAAUGAAAAGGUAUGUCCCUUAAGAGGGCUACAGAAGGCCAGGCACAGUGGCUCAUGUUUGUAAUCCCCUCACUUUGGUAGGUUGAGUCAGGAGGAUUACUUGAGGCCAGGAAUUCAAGACCAGCCUGGCCUACAUAGCAAGACCCUGUCUCUACAAAAAAAUUUUUUAAAAAACAGCUGGGCACAGUGUUGUGCACUUGUAGUCCCAGCUACUUGGGGGGCUGAGACAGAAGGACCAUUUGAGCCCAGGAGUUCAAUGUUAUAGUGUACCACUGCACUCCAGCCUGGGCAACAGAGGGAGACUCUGUCUGUAACGAAAAUAAAAAGAGGGCAAAAGAGACAAUACUGGAGACAAGCAUCUGACACAAAAUGUGAAGGGAUGUUAUGAUUGGUGGGGCUCUCUGACACCUAUCCAUAUUUACAAAUGUGCCAUUAAUCAUAUGGCCAGGUUGGAUCCUGAGUAGAUUAACAGUUACACGGGUACAGGAAUAAGGAUGCAUGUGGUAUUUUUUUUUUUUUUUUGGAGAUGGAGCUCCAUUCUUGUUGCCCAAGCUGGAGUGUAAUGGCACGAUCUUGGCUCACUGCAACCUCCACCUCCCAGGUUCAAACGAUUCUCCUGCCUCAGCCUCCCAAGUAGCUGGGAUUAGAGGUGCGCGCCACCAGGCCCAGCUAAUUUUUUGUAUUUUUAGUAGAAACGAGGUUUCACCAUGUUAGCCAGGCUGGUCUCGAACUCCUGACCUCAGGUGAUCCACCCACCUCGGCCUCCCCAGUUGCUGGGAUUACAGGUGUGAGCCACCGCACCUGGCUGCAUGUGGUAUUCUUAAUUCUUUCACAUCACACUUGAGGUGUGCAACACUCAUUGUUUCUCUGUUGUCCUGUACUCCCUUCUCAGACUCUGUUCCCAUAACCUCUGCUGGGGGGACAGCAGAUUAUGAAACCCUGUUCCCAUUCCCUUACCGAAGUUGAUCAGACAAGGGGAGAGGAGGUGGUUGUUUGACCUAAACUUGGCUAGCCAAAUUUUUUCUCCCGAAAAUUUGGAAUCAAGUCUGAGAAACUUCAAUUAGUAAAUUGUAAGGCAGAGACUAAUGAGGUAAUGUAGACUUGAGAUUGAAAGUACCCUUUUAAGAACACUGUCUUCAGUGGGGUACGGUGGCUCAUGCCCAUAAUCCCAACACUUUGGGAGGUUGAGGUGGGAGGACUGCUUGAUCCUAGAGUUCAAGACCAGCCUGGGCAACAAAGUAAGAUCCGUCUCUACAAAAAAUUUAAAAAGUUAACCAGGUGUGGUGGCAUGUGCCUGUGAUCCCAGCUACACGACAGGUGGAGGUGGAGGAUCCCUUGAGCCCAGGAGAUCGAAGCUGCAGUGAGCCCUGUUCAUGCCACUGCACUCCAGCUUGGGCAACAGAGUGAGACCCUGUCUCAAAAACAAAAGGACACUAUCUUCAGCCCAUGUGUGAUGAAGAUGCAGAUAAUGUCUGUCUGCAGAGUGUCAGAAGAAAGAAAAAAAUGUGCAAAGGGGGCAGAGAAGAGAGACCACAUAGUUUUAGGAAGACAGACAGCCCCGAGCAACCAAAGACUCUUCAGUUUCCGGAUCCUGAAGCUCAUGAGGAUAUAUGGGACACCUGCACCGGCAUUGGAUUUGGCCCCGCAACAUCUUAAAGGAACAACCUAAUACAUACCCCUUGUCUGCCUGAUCCCUGGGGAACAUGCUGUCCUGUGAUGCUGAAGCCUGCAGCUGGUGAACUCAUGGUGAACUCGUGGCCCACCUUUGGAUUCAGACAAAUCUCCCAGGGAGUAUUGGCCACCUCCCCUGGCAGACUCAGUACCCCUGGCCCCUGCUGUGGGGUUACCUUGUCUUGGUUGUGGCAGGCCUACUGGCUGUUAGUUCAGCAUCAUCCUUCAAGAGAACAGAAAGGCUUAGAAUAAUUGAUUGUCAUAUCUGUGUCUGACCAUGCUAUUGUGGACUUGGCCUGAACAGCCAUAGAAAUGCAAGGAAUGAGGUUUGAGGGACUUGGGCAGUUGUCUCAAAAAGGGAGUCAAGGCAGAAAUCCCUUACCCUGAGCACUGCUCUCAACAUGGAGGUAACUCACUGUGGUAGGCAGCCUUUUAUUUCAUGAUUUGACUUUUUGAUGAGUCCAUGCUAGUUCUCUUGUAGAAUAUUAUGCAUUCUUGAUUUGGCCAAUUAUUUCCUCAUAAUAUCUUAUAACUUGUUUCUCCAACCCUUGCCUUUUUAUUAAAAAAAAAAACUCGACAUUAUAUGUACAGAUUUGAUUAUAUUCGGGUUAAACAUUUUUAGAAAGAAUACUUCAGUAACAUUGAGUAGGUUACAUCAUUUCAUGUUAGGCACAUAAUUUCAGCUUGUCUCACUAUUAGUAACGCUAAAUUUGGUCACUUGGUUAAGAUGAUGACCCCCCCUCCCACUCUCUUCACUGAAAAAGGACACACAUCCCUUUGCACUUUAUAAGUAAUCUACAAAUAACCCGUUCAACAACUUUUCAUCUUAUACUUUGAACACCUUUUGUGAUCUUUUCCUGAGUCAAUUAUUUCACUGGGGGUUGCAAAAAUGGUGUUCUAACUAUAGUAGUCUGUAUUUAUUAACUAGCAUUUUUCUGUAAAGAAGAACUUUCUUUUUUUAAGAGACGGAGUCUAGCUCUGUCUCCCAGAUUAGAGUGCAGUGGCACUAUCAGAGCUCACUGAAGCCUCAACCUCCUGGGUGCAAGCGAUUCUCCCACCUCAGCCUUCUGUGUUGCUGGGACCACAGGCACAUGCCACCGUGCCUGGUAAGAGCGUUGUUUUAAGAAAACCAUUUUAAUGAAUUUCUCAGUGGACCACUGGGUAGUGGUUUGUUUCCAAUUUUGUUGAAAGCACUUGGAAAGCUCUUGAUUUUUAAAAGGAUUUGUUACCUAAUUAUUGGAGCUAUUCACUUUCUCAGUACUAUCCCCAAUAUUUUCAGUUAUUCCUGUGUUUGGUCCCCAGGAGGUUUUUAAAUUCAGACAACGCAGGAUUUGAGGUAAAGGUGGAAGAGAGAUUCAGCAAUCUGUGUAAGAUGGAAGAAAAGCUAAGUGGAAACCAAGAACCAGCAUGACAUCUCGACUGCACCAGUUCUCAGAAAAGCAGUUUUAGAAUGCAUACUUGUAGAAGUUGAGGAUCUAGAAAUUAGUUCCCAUAAAACUCUGCAUGCUUUGGGACCCCUUGGAAAGUUUUUACCUGAAGCCAGAGGUCUAUAGUACAGAACACUGAGCAAAGUCUUCCAGGUUUGGUUGAUGACAAGCUAAGGGCAGAAAUAAAGGAAUUUAGAGACUGGCUUUCAAAACAAUAGCCUGGAUUUCAAGCCUAUUGUCUUGUUUCUAUUUUGAAUUUCAGAAGCCAAAUAUUAAUUUCUUUUUUUCCAUUCCUUUUGUAACAUCUAAACAGUGCCAAAACACUAUCUCCAAGGCAAAUGGAUUCCCCAGGCAGAUGAGAAGAUCACAUUACUCAUGUUCAAAAUAUUACCCCAGUUGCACAAGUAUUGUGGAAUUUUGUGCAUUUGGAUGGAAGACAACUGUUUCUUUAUCUUCUUCCAAUGUCAAAAGAAGCAGGCUGUGAGCCAAGGGGAAGGCAGAGGACAGAAAUGAAUGUGUUUCCAGGCUUUCCUGGUGGUUUAUGGCAUUCUCCAAACUCCUAUGCAAGGGCUAUUCCUGACCAAGAAGAUCUAAAGAGAACGUCUCUGAAAUCAAGUCCGGAUGAAGGAGGCCUCAUUCUUCUUUUCCCCAACCAGAAUUAAGAGAAAAAAAGUGAAUAUGGUUUUUGCUCACAGAAUGGAUAACAGCAAGCCACAUUUGAUUAUUCCUACACUUCUGGUGCCCCUCCAAAACCGCAGCUGCACUGAAACAGCCACACCUCUGCCAAGCCAAUACCUGAUGGAAUUAAGUGAGGAGCACAGUUGGAUGAGCAACCAAACAGACCUUCACUAUGUGCUGAAACCCGGGGAAGUGGCCACAGCCAGCAUCUUCUUUGGGAUUCUGUGGUUGUUUUCUAUCUUCGGCAAUUCCCUGGUUUGUUUGGUCAUCCAUAGGAGUAGGAGGACUCAGUCUACCACCAACUACUUUGUGGUCUCCAUGGCAUGUGCUGACCUUCUCAUCAGCGUUGCCAGCACGCCUUUCGUCCUGCUCCAGUUCACCACUGGAAGGUGGACGCUGGGUAGUGCAACGUGCAAGGUUGUGCGAUAUUUUCAAUAUCUCACUCCAGGUGUCCAGAUCUACGUUCUCCUCUCCAUCUGCAUAGACCGGUUCUACACCAUCGUCUAUCCUCUGAGCUUCAAGGUGUCCAGAGAAAAAGCCAAGAAAAUGAUUGCGGCAUCGUGGGUCUUUGAUGCAGGCUUUGUGACCCCUGUGCUCUUUUUCUAUGGCUCCAACUGGGACAGUCAUUGUAACUAUUUCCUCCCCUCCUCUUGGGAAGGCACUGCCUACACUGUCAUCCACUUCUUGGUGGGCUUUGUGAUUCCAUCUGUCCUCAUAAUUUUAUUUUACCAAAAGGUCAUAAAAUAUAUUUGGAGAAUAGGCACAGAUGGCCGAACGGUGAGGAGGACAAUGAACAUUGUCCCUCGGACAAAAGUGAAAACUAUCAAGAUGUUCCUCAUUUUAAAUCUGUUGUUUUUGCUCUCCUGGCUGCCUUUUCAUGUAGCUCAGCUAUGGCACCCCCAUGAACAAGACUAUAAGAAAAGUUCCCUUGUUUUCACAGCUAUCACAUGGAUAUCCUUUAGUUCUUCAGCCUCUAAACCUACUCUGUAUUCAAUUUAUAAUGCCAAUUUUCGGAGAGGGAUGAAAGAGACUUUUUGCAUGUCCUCUAUGAAAUGUUACCGAAGCAAUGCCUAUACUAUCACAACAAGUUCAAGGAUGGCCAAAAAAAACUACGUUGGCAUUUCAGAAAUCCCUUCCAUGGCCAAAACUAUUACCAAAGACUCGAUCUAUGACUCAUUUGACAGAGAAGCCAAGGAAAAAAAGCUUGCUUGGCCCAUUAACUCAAAUCCACCAAAUACUUUUGUCUAAGUUCUCAUUCUUUCAAUUGUUAUGCACCAGAGAUUAAAAAGCUUUAACUAUAAAAA